AUUUGGGAAGUUGGCUGGCUGGCGAGGCAGAGCCUCUCCUCAAAGCCUGGCUCCCACGGAAAAUAUGCUCAGUGCAGCCGCGUGCAUGAAUGAAAACGCCGCCGGGCGCUUCUAGUCGGACAAAAUGCAGCCGAGAACUCCGCUCGUUCUGUGCGUUCUCCUGUCCCAGGGCCAAACAACCCACCUGCACUGCAUGGUUCCCCCAGCAAGAACAUCCCAGUGAGAAUGGCCCACAGAUGCCUGGGCGUGACCCACCUGCAGCUUCAACCAUGCAGGUGCUGCUGCUAACAUCUGCAGAAGAUUUGGACUGCACUCCUGGAUUUCAGCAGAAAGUGUUCCAUAUCAAUCAGCCAGCUGAAUUCAUUGAGGACCAGUCAAUUCUAAACUUGACCUUCAGUGACUGUAAGGGAAACGACAAGCUACGCUAUGAGGUCUCGAGCCCAUACUUCAAGGUGAACAGCGAUGGCGGCUUAGUUGCUCUGAGAAACAUAACUGCAGUGGGCAAAACUCUGUUCGUCCAUGCACGGACCCCCCAUGCGGAAGAUAUGGCAGAACUCGUGAUUGUCGGGGGGAAAGACAUCCAGGGCUCCUUGCAGGAUAUAUUUAAAUUUGCAAGAACUUCUCCUGUCCCAAGACAAAAGAGGUCCAUUGUGGUAUCUCCCAUUUUAAUUCCAGAGAAUCAGAGACAGCCUUUCCCAAGAGAUGUUGGCAAGGUAGUCGAUAGUGACAGGCCAGAAAGGUCCAAGUUCCGGCUCACUGGAAAGGGAGUGGAUCAAGAGCCUAAAGGAAUUUUCAGAAUCAAUGAGAACACAGGGAGCGUCUCCGUGACACGGACCUUGGACAGAGAAGUAAUCGCUGUUUAUCAACUAUUUGUGGAGACCACUGAUGUCAAUGGCAAAACUCUCGAGGGGCCGGUGCCUCUGGAAGUCAUUGUGAUUGAUCAGAAUGACAACCGACCGAUCUUUCGGGAAGGCCCCUACAUCGGCCACGUCAUGGAAGGGUCACCCACAGGCACCACAGUGAUGCGGAUGACAGCCUUUGAUGCAGAUGACCCAGCCACCGAUAAUGCCCUCCUGCGGUAUAAUAUCCGUCAGCAGACGCCUGACAAGCCAUCUCCCAACAUGUUCUACAUCGAUCCUGAGAAAGGAGACAUUGUCACUGUUGUGUCACCUGCGCUGCUGGACCGAGAGACUCUGGAAAAUCCCAAGUAUGAACUGAUCAUCGAGGCUCAAGAUAUGGCUGGACUGGAUGUUGGAUUAACAGGCACGGCCACAGCCACGAUCAUGAUCGAUGACAAAAAUGAUCACUCACCAAAAUUCACCAAGAAAGAGUUUCAAGCCACAGUCGAGGAAGGAGCUGUGGGAGUUAUUGUCAAUUUGACAGUUGAAGAUAAGGAUGACCCCACCACAGGUGCAUGGAGGGCUGCCUACACCAUCAUCAACGGAAACCCCGGGCAGAGCUUUGAAAUCCACACCAACCCUCAAACCAACGAAGGGAUGCUUUCUGUUGUCAAACCAUUGGACUAUGAAAUUUCUGCCUUCCACACCCUGCUGAUCAAAGUGGAAAAUGAAGACCCACUCGUACCCGACGUCUCCUACGGCCCCAGCUCCACAGCCACCGUCCACAUCACUGUCCUGGAUGUCAACGAGGGCCCAGUCUUCUACCCAGACCCCAUGAUGGUGACCAGGCAGGAGGACCUCUCUGUGGGCAGCGUGCUGCUGACAGUGAAUGCCACGGACCCCGACUCCCUGCAGCAUCAAACCAUCAGGUAUUCUGUUUACAAGGACCCAGCAGGUUGGCUGAAUAUUAACCCCAUCAAUGGGACUGUUGACACCACAGCUGUGCUGGACCGUGAGUCCCCAUUUGUCGACAACAGCGUGUACACUGCUCUCUUCCUGGCAAUUGACAGUGGCAACCCUCCCGCUACGGGCACUGGGACUUUGCUGAUAACCCUGGAGGACGUGAAUGACAAUGCCCCGUUCAUUUACCCCACAGUAGCUGAAGUCUGUGAUGAUGCCAAAAACCUCAGUGUAGUCAUUUUGGGAGCAUCAGAUAAGGAUCUUCACCCGAAUACAGAUCCUUUCAAAUUUGAAAUCCACAAACAAGCUGUUCCUGAUAAAGUCUGGAAGAUCUCCAAGAUCAACAAUACACACGCCCUGGUAAGCCUUCUUCAAAAUCUGAACAAAGCAAACUACAACCUGCCCAUCAUGGUGACAGAUUCAGGGAAACCACCCAUGACGAAUAUCACAGAUCUCAGGGUACAAGUGUGCUCCUGCAGGAAUUCCAAAGUGGACUGCAACGCGGCAGGGGCCCUGCGCUUCAGCCUGCCCUCAGUCCUGCUCCUCAGCCUCUUCAGCUUAGCUUGUCUGUGAGAACUCCUGACGUCUGAAGCUUGACUCCCAAGUUUCCAUAGCAACAGGAAAAAAAAAAAUCUAUCCAAAUCUGAAGAUUGCGGUUUACAGCUAUCGAACUUCACAACUAGGCCUCAAUUGUUCCGGUUUUUUAUUUUCUUUACAAUUUCACUUAGUCUGUACUUCAUCAUUUUGACAGCAUCUUCCUCCCUCCUUUAAUUAAUGGAAUCUUCUGAAUUUUCCCUGAAUGUUUAAAGAUCAUGACAUAUGACUUGAUCUUCUGGGAGCAGGAACAAUGACUACUUUUUCUGGUGUGUUAACAUGUCGCUAGCCAGUGCUCCAGGCACCCAGCUUUGUCUGUGGGUUAGUAUUGGUGUAUGUAUGAGUAUCUGUAUGUAUAUAUACACGGUAUUUAUAGAGAGAGACUAUCCUGGAGAAGCCUCGUUUUGAUGCCAUUCUUCCUUGCAAGGUUAAGCAAGGUGGGUGGAAACUAAGACACCUGAACCCUCCAGGGCCUCCCGCAUCAAGGUCAGCAUGAGGACAGACCACAGAGCUGUCACUUUUGCUCCGAAGCUACUUCUCCACUGUCCCGUUCAGUCUGAAUGCUGCCACAACCAGCCAGGCAGGUCCACAGAGAGGGAGAGCAGAGAAAGAAGUCCUUUCUCUUUAUUGAGUUCGAGGACUACAACCAAUUUACACUGCCAUCUGAUGCCGUGAUCCUGAGCCAAGGAGGUGAGGAGCAGAGCAGGCAAUUUCACCACCAAAUGCCAAGAAAAGGGCUGACAUUUUCUUUCAUGGGCACCAACCUGCAUUUGUAUGUGUCCCGAAUCCACAGUCGUACUGAUUCUAAUGGGGACACAGAUCAUGGUAGAGAAUCUCUCCCUCCUCAGUAAAUGUACAACUGCACCUGUCAUCAUGGAGGUCAUACAUGCAUACAAAGAGGUGUACAGGUACCAUCUUGUAUACACAUAUAUACCCACAUGUACAGACAUACAUUUAUGCACAUUCACGCUGUUUGUUUCAUAUAUACAGGCAUAAAAUAGAGUAAAUACAGGUAGUUUUAAAAGUACCCUUUUGUGUGAAUUGACUACCGUUGUUUGCAAACCCGAAAAUAAAAGACGUUCAUUAUGUAUGAAAAGUAACUGAUUUGUAUUCUGUGAGCAUGUAAAAGCGGAAAGUUAGUGCUUGUUCUAAGAUUACCUUCUUGUUGAUAAACCAUAAAUGAAUCAUCAAAGCUCACACCAAAUUUUUCUAUCAAAUAAAACUAGUGACAGCUUGUGGCUUUUUAUUAGAGCUCGCCACGAACUAGGGUAAGGUGAGUGUCUUAGCAUAUUUUAAUGCAGUUGCUUACUAAAGGUUUUAACCGCACAUGCACACACACACGCUUUCUUAUGCAAUCUAUGUUUGCACUUGUGCUUUCAGUUAGCCUUCUGUAGGAAGUAGAAGUCAUAUGUUGUCUUUGUUGUAGUGAAAUUAUACAGAUAGAGUUCCAUAUAUUGUAUUUGUUUCAAUGGUAAAUCCUUUUGGAACAUAUAGAAUGCAGAGAUUUUUUUUUCCAUUAAAAUAAAUGGGUAUUGGUGGUUAAAACUGCUGGACAGUAACUGUUCUCUGAUUUCUAUCUUGUGUCCAAUGUCACUGAUGUUGGGUCUUGUCUUAGUGCAAGUUCACAUUUUUGACAGACCAUUUGGGGUCCGUCGUACAUCUCUGGUUGGUGAGUGAGUCUAUGAAGACAGAAGUACCAGUUCUCAGCAUGGGCCAUGGACUCAUCUUGUCCACCUCAUGAUAUGAUCUGAGGGUGUCAUAAUCAGCUAUAAAGGUAAUUGCAUACUCAAAGAUGAGACGGACCAUUCUCAGUUGAUGACCACAUUAAGCAUAGUCAUGGCCAUCUGUCAACAGUCCCAAGACCUGGGGAUUUUUCUCUGGAACAAAUCCUGUUGCUGGAUCAGGAGAUGCCACACCUUGAACUUGAUAGGGUCAUUCUCCACGAGCACAUGCCCCCGACUCAGGGACAGGGGAAUCUAAGCCUGUGCAUUCACACUCCACAAGAUUUCCUCUACUGGCUUUACAGGGCACUGUCACGCGUCUCCCGGGCGCACCUUGCUCCCCUCUUCCUGCAAGGCAGGGGGAGAACGUUCAUCCUUGAACAAACAAAGAGCAUCCUCAGCCAGUCAGGCGGCUGGUAGCCGGACACAUAUGCUAACUGGCAAUCAGGAAGUCACCCUCCAAUGUAAACUUCAGCCACAUGCAGGGAGAAACACAGCAGCUGAGUGGCCAUUCACUCAAGGAAACAAAUACAGCAUGACUCCUUUUCUCUCAAGCUGGUAGGCUCUCCUGCACUUUGUGAACCGAACCAGAAGAUUAACUUCGCUGAAAAUUCAGAAAAAUAGGAGUAAAGUGCACACUUCAUUAAUAAAUAGAAUAUGCCUCAACUUUCCCUUAUUUAAACAUAUUCUCUGUCCCCACAGUUCUAAUCAGGACAGAGAUACUUCUGUCAUGUUGUUCCUCCUAAUAGUUUCCAGAAAAAAAGGAAAAUAAACCAAUUCUUAUAGGCCAAAGUGGUAGCAUUUCCUGAAUCAUAAGAUGUUUUGUUCAUUUGCUGGAAUAUAUUACAUUGUUUACUGAAAACCAUAGUAGAAUCAAAAUGUUAUUUCAUUAUUACCUAUGCAUUUUAUCUGAGUCCAACUUAUUAAAAAACGAAGUCAAGUAAGGACCAGAAAUUGCUUUUCCCAAUUACUGAGCACAGGUCUGAGGGUUUUAUUUCCACUGAGCAAAUAGUCACACCUUCACUUCUUUUUAUUAAUACUCAACCAACUUAGUUGAUUAAAAAUCACAUUUUCUCCCUCAUUUUACAUACGAUAAAUUAAUUAUUUUGGAUAAUUUGUUUUAAUAAGAAUAUGCACACAUUUUCUAAUUUCAAUAAAAGUCACCUUCAAUACCGCCAGUUCUCUCCAAAUGAGCAUCAUUCCAGGCAGAUAUACCUGCUGUGCCUCUUGGCCGACACCAGCAAAUCUAAGCAUUAUAACGAAAUAAAUCCAGCCAGAUUUCAUGGUAGGUAUCAAAUAAGACUUUGGCUCUUAAAGAACAUCGUUAGAAAUUUUGAUAGCUCAUUCCAGAGUUUCAGAAUGUCAUUUAAAACAGUCUGAUAAAUGGAACAACCAUCUACCAUCACACUCAUAGAGUAGCUCAAAUUGCAUUUUACCCAAAUAAAUACACUGGGUCUUAAUCUUAAGAUGUGACAACUAAAAAAUUUUUAACAAGUCUGUGUUUGAUCCUGGAUUUAGUGCAGUUGCACCCAGGCACGAGCUCUCCAGAUGAUUCUGAGGAAAGGAGUCUACAAUUUUCCUAGGGGGUGUAUGAACAUGGUACCAAAAAGGUGAUUAAUAAUUAUAAUAAUGGUUUAUAUUUAUCAACUGCUUAUUAUGUGCCCACACUGUACAAAAUCCUUACAGAUAGUAACUCAUUAAUCCCUCCAGUAACAUAUGAGACAAGCACUACUAUCUUCUCCAACUCACAGAUAAAGAAGGCUGAGGCUCAGAAAAAUUGAAUGGCUUGCCCAAGGUAAGUGGCCUCCAGAACCAAACCUCAGGCUAUCUGGCUCCAGGGUUCAUGUUCUUCCGACAACAUCACAAUGCCACUCUCAACCCAGGAGCAAAACCAGACAAAGUGCCUACUGCAGACCGGAAGACCCUCGUUUGAAGCCUCCAUUAGCGUGACUAUGCAGCUAGACCAACUUACUGUUAAGCAACAGUACCUUUUACUAUGAGGUACCCUUUACUAUUAAGUACCUUUUACUAACAGUAUCUUCUGUUACCUAUUAUUAAGUUCAUGCUAUACUUCUUCAAUCUGAAAGCUUUCUGUUAAAAAAAAAAAUGUUAACAUCGUUCUAAAUUAAUAUUGAGACCUUAGAAAUUUUUCCUGUGCAAGAUAACGUAAUUAUUUGCCCCUUCCCUUCCAUGGCUUGUUAGCAGGUAGAUGAGGGGCUUCUCCUAGAUUAAUUUAACAUCUCAGUUAAUCAAAAGUAGCCGGGCAUGGUGACUCAUGCCUGUAAUCCCAGCCCUUUGGGAGGCAGAGGCGGGUGGAUCACUUAAGGUCAGGAGUUCAAGACCAGCCUGGCCAGCAUGGUGAAACCCUAUCUCUACUAAAAAAUACAAAAAUUAGCUGGGUGUGGUGGUGCACACCUGAAACCCCAGCUACUCAGGAGGCUGAGGCAGGAGAAUCGCUUGAACCCAGGAGGCAGAGUUUGCAGUGAGCCAUUGCACUCCAGCCUGGGCAACAGAGCAAGACUCCGUCAAAAAAAAAAAAAAAAAAAAAGAAAGAAAAGGAAAUUUAUGAACUCCAGAGUACCCAUUCACUACCAAACCAACUGAGGGGAGAGAAAACUGAGGGAGAAAGUGGGGUGGGGUCUCAAAGGGUUUGCACUGUGCUUUGCUAUAAAUCAUUCAAAGGGGCAAAUUCUAAAGGAUCUCUAAGUAGUUGCUGAUUUUGUAAAGGUAGCCCAUAAAUCUGUUUACGUGUAGCUGCCUUAAACAUGAGUCAACAGGGUAAGUCACACCAACAGGAAACCCAAGCACUAAAAAAGCCACCUACCUUUUCUGUUUACCAAAUACUAAGAAUAAUAAUCUAAUAAUCUGGCUACAUCUUUCAUAAAGACCUCCAUCUUCUCUCCUUAACUGACUGUUGAGAUUUGAUAAUUUUCACAGUCUAAUGAUAAAAUGCUUUCAAAAUGGUUCAUCUAACACAAUUAACAAUUCUUUUACUAUAUGCAAUGUGUUACCCUUACUAUAUUUCCUAUUGCUAAUAGAUUAGCCCACUAUUGAAAAAAUUCUGCAGUUGUGACCGUGUUCACAUGAAAGCAUAUACAAGACAUGGAGAGACAGCAAAAAAUGGUGGGAAUGGGUGUGUGUAUGAGGGUUUCAGAUAAGAACUUCAAUUAUAUAAUUUAAGAAGAGUCAGUCUAUAAUUUAAGCAGAAAUAAUUGAGAUACUCAUCAAAUUAAGUAAGCGGAAAAAUUUCCUCUCUCUCAUACUAUGUUGCUAUCAUCACAUCUAUCGUUGGAGGGUUGCUGAGCUUGAUACGCCUUUGAACCAUUUUAUUUGACUUUCCACGUGCCGUCUCAUUGGUAGGGAGAUGGUGAAAAGCGUUGGGUGGUGUAGGACGAGGGAGGUUUUCACUCUGAAGCUAUGAAGAUUUGGAGAAAGGGGCUUAUAGAAGCACUAUGAAAAUAAACUGGAGACUAUUUUUUUGCUACUUUUUAAAAAGCUUUUUCUUUAGAGAGUACUAAAGCCAUUCUAUAUCUGUCGUACACAUGAAUUCAGACUAUUAUUAGAGAGUUAUAUCUGUGUUGUCAUGCACAUGUCAACACUGUCCUGAUGACAAAAUUUUAUGUAUCCCCCCAGAUAAAAAUUUUAAGAAAUUUUAAAUGCUUUUUAUUCACACACACUUUUCAAAAGGGAUAAAAGUUAAUCAUGUUAAAAUAUUCAGUCUAUGGCAGAUGUCGCUCCUUUGGGCCCUCACUGCUGAAUUGCUUACAGUUUCUGAGCUGUAAACUAACAUUUGCUUUACUAUGUAGUUACAGAGAAAUGUGCAACUUGUUUGUGAAACAUUCAAAUAAAGCUUAUCUGGGAUUUUUAA